AAUAGGAAGUGAGAACAUCCCCGAGCAAGACCAACAAUUGCUGAAUAAACACAAACCCCCUUGAGAAUCACGCCGACAGGUGCUAUCUCUUCACCUGGGGAUUGCAAAGGAAGUGAGAACAUCCCCGAGCAAGACCAAAAAUUGCUGAAUAAACACAAACCCCCUUGAGAAUCACGCCAAGAGGUGCUGCCUCUUCACCUGGGGAUUGCAAAGCCUCACCGCCAUGGACAGCGUGCCCCUCAUCUGUGACUACGGCUCUGGCUUCAGCAAGGUGGGAUUUGCAGGAAUGGAAAGCCCAAUGGGCAUGUUCCCCACUGUCCUCGGGAAACUUCGGCACGAUAAUGUAUUGGUGGGGAUGGAAGAGGAAGACUGGUUCAUUGGAGAGGAGGUUCAGAAAAAAUGAGGGAAACUCAACCUGCAAUACCCCAUUUCUCGGGCAAUAACAACCAACUGGGACAACAUGGAGAAGAUUUGGCACCACUCCUUCUACCAGGUGCUCCACGUCGCCCCAGAGCAGUACCCCAUGUUGGUGACGGAGCCGUCUUUGAACCCAACACCCAGCAAAGAGAAAGUCACACAGGUGCUGUUUGAGAUUUUCAACAUACCUGCCCUGUAUUUAGCUAACCGAGGAGUCCUUUCUCUGUACGCCUCUGGCCAGACCUUCGGCAUGACUGUUGAAUCUGGAGAAGGAAUGACACACUUCGUGCCCAUCGCUGAUGGCUGUCCUUUGCAUCAGUCAACCUUCCAGGUGGACAUAGCGGGCCAGGACCUAACCUCGUACCUCCUGCAACUGUUGAAAGACAAUGUGCAAUUAUUGGUGGGCACAGGGGAUCGAGAGUACAUCCGGGACAUGAAGGAGAAAUGCUGCUAUGUGGCUUUGGACUUUGACAAGGAAAAGAUGAAAACUGAUUCACCUUCAUGCCAACAGAAAUAUCAGCUGCCUGAUGGCCAAGAGAUCACCGUUGGGCAGGAGAGCUUCUUCUGCCCCGAGGGAAAAACACCCCUGGCAUCCACACGAAGGCCAUCCAGAGCAUCACUUCCUGCAACCCCGACCUCCAGAAGGUUCUCUUUGGCCACAUGCUACUGUCCGGAGGGACGGGCUCCUGCCCCGGCUUGCGAUUCCGGAUGCAGAGAGAAAUAUCUGAGCUGGUGUCCCCUACAGUUUAUGUGAAGGUGGCCACCUGUCCGUAUUCUGUCUAUGGAGCUUGGGUAGGUGGCUCCAUCUUGUGCUCACUCUCCACGUUCAAGGAUAUGUGGGUCACCAGCAAGGAGUACAAGGAGAUGGGCUCUUCCAUCAUCAGUAGAAAAAGCUUCUGAUGUGUGGCUUUCAGGACCAUGUUGCCUGUGCCUUCGACACCAACUGCAGGAUGAGCCUUGUUGUGGCUGAAUUGAACAGAGCUCAGAACCAGCUCAAGGGCAAAGGCACUUCCUCCCCCAGACUUCAAUAAAGAAGGUCAAUAAAG